UUUUUUUUUUUUAAACAAUAAAUAAGUUGAAAUUAAUAUACAGGCUACCAGAUCAGCCAGGCAGAAGAAAGAUCUCAGGGACAAAUAGUACUGUCCUCAAAACACCAUCAGGAAAGAGCCAUAUAUAUCUGCAUUGCCACUGUAUAUUUCUAUUUUCUAUACCCAACUAAGCCAAAUAAAGUUCAUGGUAUUGGAGAGGCGGCUCUACUACAAUGACACGUUUAGAUUUACCUAUUUGUAAUUUUAGCUGUAAGUAGUAUAGAUUUGAUUAUCAUCUUUAAUAUUGGCUAUUGAAUAGGGACAGAAUAGACUUAGCUUUUAUGGGGAUAAGUCAUUUCUGUUCACGAAGAUCUUAUAGUAUCUUAUGGGUAAGAUAUAUGUAUCUAGGUAUCUAGGUUUUUUGUCUCUCAGCAAUAAAGAAAAAUCAUGAAUGAACCCCUCCUUACAGUCCUGCAAAAAAGUGAACCUAUCUGUUGUUUGGAAACAUUAAAAUAGAGAGAAUGUUCCCAUCUGCAGGGGACAGUUUAUGUGAAGUUAUUCUUGAAGACAGGGAAAGGGCUUAGAUGACCCCUGGGAAGCCCCUCUCCCAACUCUCCAGCAGCAACCUCCCCUGGUAAGCCUACAGGUAUCUUCUUCCGUCUAUGCUGCUUUCGUGUGAAGGGUAAUAGUUAUGACACCUAUGGCAAUUCCAGAAAUGCAUGUGUACCACUGAAUGCCACUUUUGUCUCUUUAGGAGGGUGAGACUCAGACUUUGUGGCACUUAGCAGUAACUUUGAUAACUCAAAAGAGGCAAAUGCGUAUCAGAAUUUUCCCCUCUCACAGAGCCCUGGCAAGAUUAUUUUUCUCCUGCAGUGAUGAAAUAGAACAUUAAAUAUUCUGUCUUCUCCAAACAAAAAGCAUAAUACAAUCCCUUUUUAUCUGACAGUUGACCGAAACUUGUUUUUCUGGGUUCAUCAGUUAUCUUUUUAUUUUAUUUAUUUAUUUGUAUUUAUUUAUUUAUUUUUUUAGAGACGGAGUCUCACUCUGUCACCCAGGCUGGAGUGGAGUGGCGCGAUCUCACUGCAAGCUCCACCUCCCGGGUUCACGCCAUUCUCCUGCCUCAGCCUCCCGAGUAGCUGGGACGCCACUAAGCCCAGCUAAUUUUUUUUUUUGUUUUGUAUUUUUAGUAGAGACAUGGUUUCACUGUGUUGGCCGGGAUGGUCUUGAUCUCCUGACCUCGUGAUCCGACCGCCUCAGCCUCCCAAAGUGCUGGGAUUAUAGGCGUGAGCCACCGCACCAGCCCAGUUACUUUUUUUAAUAGAUGGCAGAUAAAAUUAGAGAUGAGACAAUGCAUGGCGAAGAAUGUCUCUUUCUAUGAAAAGCGGAAGACCUAAAACUAAACCCAGCCAGAAAACACUUUCCAUGCACAGAUAACAUCACUUAUCGAUUUAUGUCUCUGCGAGGUAAAAGAACUGCAUAUAGUCACUUAUGGAUGCUAUAAGCCAGUGGACAAAAAUAAUAUUAAAGAGAGAGACAAAGAAAAAUAUUGGGAAACUUUUAGAUUCCAGGACUGGCGUCCACCCUGCACCCUGAACUGCUGAGACAGUUCACAGCCAUCUGCAAUCCUGAGUGGGAAUAAGCGGAUAAAUUAUUAUCUUACUUGUUUUUAUUCAUCUUAAAUGUAUAUAUAACUUGCAUUUAUUUCAAUGUUUAAUAAUAGAAAGGUUUUGGUCUUUUUUUAGAAGUUUGGUAAUAUUCUUGUGACCAGAAAUAUGCCAUAGGAAAUUAACUCUUGUUUCUAUCAAUUAUUGUACAAUAAAGAUGUUUUUAUUAUUAUUUAUUUAUUUUAGUUAUUUAUUUAUUAUUUGAGACAGAGUCUGACCCUGUCACCCAGGCUGAAGCGCAGUGGUGUGAUCUCGGCUCACUGCAACCUCCACCUCUUCUGCCUCAGCCUCCCAAGUAGCUAUGAACUACAGGUACAUGCCACCACGCCUGGUUAAUUUUUGUAUUUUCAGUAGAGAUGGAGUUUUGCCAUGUUGGCCAGGCUGGUCUCGAACUCCUGACCUCAAGUAAUCCACCCACCUUGACUUCCCAAAGGGUUGGAAUUAUAGGCAUGAGCCACCACACUCAGCCAAGUUGUUUUCAUUAUAUGUCAUUUGGUGUAGUCUCAAUGUCCAAGAACCUAUGGGUGACCUUAAGUGAAGCUUUACUGUACUUUUUAGGCUCGUUCCUAGCUCAGCAGUAAAAGUGGAGAUCCCUCAGACAUGCUCUCUGUUGUUACUAAGGGCUAAAAAAAAACAAAGCCUAGCACAUAUUUUUAAAUUUUUAGGUCUAAUCCUAAAUCAAUUUUGUCACCUUUCUCAUGCCUCCUGUUUUGGGACCCCUUACACACAUAUGCAAUUGGGUACCCCACAGUCAGGGCCAUCUCACCUUCAACCUCAUCAGUGCCCUACAUCAGUAAGGGUACCUUGUACAACCCUAUCCUUUUGCUGCCACAAAUGUUAUAUUAGAUGUUUAUAGUCAAAUACAGACUAUAGAGUAAAAAGUGUCCCAAUUUUUUCUUUGUCUUUCUUUUCAAUAUCAUUUCUGUCCACUGUCCUGUGGUAUCCAUAAUUGAUUAUAGCUGCAGUUCUUUUAGCUCAAUUGAUAAGUGAUGUUUUAUGUGAUUUGGAAAGUGUUUUCUGUUAGGUUUCAGUUUUACAUCUCCCAAUUUUCAUAAAAAGAGACAUUCUUUGCCUUGGGCUGACUCAUCUCUCAAUUCUUCUGCUAUCUCUUAUCUAUGACACACACCCACACUCACUCAUAUAGGAACCAUAUAGACAUGGCAGUUCACCUCAUGUGCACAGCUUUGGGAUGUAGGGGAGGAAACUGGAAUACCCAGAGAAAACCCACACAGACAUGAAGAGAACACGCAAUUGCCACUCAGACAGUGGCAUUGAGAGAUGACAGCGUGCUGGCAGCCCUCGCUCACUCUCGGUGCCUCCUCGGCCUCGGUGCCCACUUUGGCCAUGCUCGAGGAGCCCUUCACUCCACCACUGCACUGUGGGAGCCCAUCUGUGGGCUGGCCGAGGCCGGAGCCAGCUCCCUCUGCUUGCGGGGAGGUGUGGAGGGAGAGGUGUGGGCAGGAACUGGGGCUGCACAUGGUGCUCGCGGGCCAGCGUGAGUUCCUGGUGGGCAUGGGCUCUGAGGCCCAGCACUCAGAGCAGCUGGCCAGCGCUGCCACCCCGGGCAGUGAGGGGCUUAGCACCCGGGCCAGCAGCUGUGGAGGGUGCACCGGGUCCCCCAGCAGUGCCGGCCCACAGACGCUGUGCUCAAAUUCUCGCCAGGCCUCAGCUGCCUCCCCGCAGGGCAGGGCUUGGGACCUGCAGCCCACCAUGCCCGAGCCUCCACCCUGCUGUGGGCUCCAGCAUGCAGCUGGAGCCUCCCUGAUGAGUGUCACCCCCUGCUCCCCAGAACCCAAUCCCAUUGACUGCCCAAGGGCUGAGGAGUGCGGGCGCACGGCGCCAGACUGGCGGGCAGCUCCACUUGCAGCUCCCAUGCGGGAUCCACUAGGUGAAGCCAGCUGGGCUCCUAAGUCUAGUGGGGACUUGGAGAACCUGUAUGUCUAACUAAGGGAUUGUAAAUACACCAAUCAGCACUCUGUGUCUAGCUCAAGGUUUGUAAACACACCAGUCAGCACCCUGAGUCUAGCUGAAGGUUUGUAAAUGCACCUAUCAGUGCUCUCUGUCUAGCUAAUCUAGUGGGGACUUGGAGAACUUUUGUGUCUAGCUCAGGGAUUGUAAACGCACCAAUCAGCACCCUGUCAAAAUGGACCAAUCAGCUCUCCGUAAAACAGACCAAUCAGCUCUCUGUAAAAUGGACCAAUCAGCAGGAUGUGGGUGGGGCCAGAUAAGGGAAUAAAAGCAGGCUGCCCGAGCCAGCAGUGGCAACCCACUGGGGUCCUUUUCCAUAACGUGGGAGGUUUGUUCUUUUGCUCUUCGCAAUAAAUCUUGCUGUUGCUCACUCUCUGGGUCCACACUGCCUUUAUGAGCUGCUACACUCACUUCAAAGGUCUGCAGCUUCACUUCUGAAGCCAGCGAGACCACAAACCCACUGGGAGGAAUGAACAACUCUGGAUGGGAAGAAUGAACAACUCCAGACAUGACGCUUUAAGAGCUGUAACACUCACUGUGAAGGUCUGCACCUUCACUCCUGAAGCCAGCAAGACCACGAACCCAUCAGAAGGAAGAAACUCGGAACACGUCCAAACAUCAGAAGGAACAAACUCUGGACACACCAUCUUUAAGAACUGUAACAUUCACCACGAGGAUCCGCGGCUUCAUUGUUGAAGUCAGUGAGACCAAGAACCCACCGAUUCCGGCCACAGCCUUGCAGAGACUAUAUGUAUUUUUUCUUAUCAACAUAUCGUUGAAGAAAAUUACACUACUGGGAGGCAUGCUGUAGCAAAAUGGGCUGGCAAAAAGCCAGAGCUGUUCUGAAGAUACAGCAGCUAGCCCAGUUCCUAAGGUGCUGAUUUAGAGUGACUUUGGAGUGUCCACUUACUGAAGUGUAAAAUCGCUAAAGGAGAUUUUGGUGGGAGUCGGAGUAAGCUGCUUAAUUUUGGGCAUGUUAAUUUAGAGACAGCUAUUUAGGACAUAUGUGGAGAGGGCACGCAGGCAGUUGGAGACACGAGUUCAGGGAGCGUUCUAGGCUGUGGACGUAGAUUUGGGAGUUGGUGGUAUGUAAAUAGAAUUUAUAAACAUGAGACUGAGUGAAAGCAUCAUAGCAGAGGGAAUGUUUAAAGAAGAGAGGAGGCCUGGGGAUGUUUAACGCUUAGAGGCACAGGUAUGAGGAGCCUGUGAAGCAGAAUGAGAAGUGUCACCAAUUGAGGCAGAAGGAGAAUAGUGAGGAAGUGGAAGCUACAGAAGAAAGUGUUUCAGGAAGGAAGGAGUUACCAGCUGUGACACAUGUGGUUUAGGACAAGUGAGUUGAGCCUUGAAAAUUGGCCAUUGGCUUCAGAAAAGUGUAGUAGUUGGUGAAGUUGAAGAAAGCUGCUUUUAGUGUGGUGUUGGGAACAAUGCCUGGCAGAAUUGGGCUCAAGAAACAAUAGAACAAGGCAAGGUGGAGACAGCAAAUACAGGCAAAUGUGUUGGGCAGAUAUUCAGGUGGUUACCAAGUAGGCAGGUAGAAAAACUAUUUUGGUAGAAAACUGGGUGAUUGGAAAUGUUGGCAUUUCAGGAGUUGCAUUUGGUUUAGAGACAUAAAUACCAUUCAGGGGGACAAGUCCUCUGAAGAGGUAUCUAGUAUAAUUGCAUCUGAGAACAAAAACCAGGGGAAAACAAACCAUAAACCACGGGCUAGAGUAGAGGGUCCCAGACAUUAAGAUAUAUAAAAGGGCCGGGCGCGAUGGCUUAUGCUUGUAAUCCCAGCACUUUGGGAGGCUGAGGCGGGCAGAUCACGAGGUCAGAAGAUCGAGACCAUCCAGGCUAACAUGGUGAAACCCCGUCUCUACUAAAAAUACAAAACAUUAGCCAGGUGUGGUGGUGGGUGCCUGUAGUUCCAGCUACUCAGGAAACUGAGGCAGGAGAAUGGCCUGAACCUGGGAGGCGGAGCUUGCAGUGAGCCGAGAUCCCGCCACUGCACUCCAGCUUGGACAACAGAGCGAGACUCCGUCUCAAAAAAAAAAAAAAAAAAAAAAAAGAUAUAUCAAAGGUGAUGGAAAUCCAGCUGAAUUGAUAAUGCAGAUGAGUAGAGAGAAGAUAAAUUCAGCAAGAUGAGAGGA